GCUUUCCAACCGGACUUUGGGGCUAGCGUUUAGAAAAGUCUCGACCUCCUCCGGCCCGGUCCCAUCCCAAGAACCGACUAAGGCUGUGAGUGUCCGGGAACCAGACCCGCUUGGAGGCCACAGCCCCGACGUCCCGCGCCCACGCGGCAGAUCGGGCGCUGCGGCCUGGGAGCCUCGGGGAGAUGCGGAGCAGGAGCAAUUCCGGGGUCCGCUUGGACGGGUACGCGCGGCUGGUGCAGCAAACCAUCCUGUGUUACCAGAAUCCCGUCACGGGGCUGCUGUCAGCCAGCCAUGAGCAGAAGGAUGCCUGGGUGCGGGAUAACAUCUACAGUAUCCUGGCCGUGUGGGGCCUGGGCAUGGCCUACCGUAAGAAUGCAGACCGCGAUGAGGACAAGGCCAAGGCCUACGAGCUGGAGCAGAACGUGGUGAAGCUGAUGCGAGGUCUUCUCCAGUGCAUGAUGAGACAGGUGGCCAAAGUGGAGAAGUUCAAACACACUCAGAGCACCAAGGACAGCCUGCACGCCAAGUACAACACCGCCACCUGUGGCACGGUGGUGGGCGACGACCAGUGGGGCCACCUCCAGGUGGAUGCCACCUCUCUCUUCCUCCUGUUCCUGGCCCAGAUGACCGCCUCAGGCUUACGUAUCAUUUUCACUCUCGAUGAGGUGGCCUUCAUACAGAAUCUUGUCUUUUACAUAGAAGCUGCAUAUAAAGUCGCUGAUUAUGGAAUGUGGGAGCGUGGAGAUAAGACUAAUCAGGGCAUCCCGGAAUUGAAUGCAAGCUCCGUAGGAAUGGCCAAGGCAGCUCUUGAGGCAAUUGAUGAACUGGACCUUUUUGGAGCCCAUGGAGGACGCAAGUCAGUGAUUCAUGUUCUGCCAGAUGAGGUCGAGCACUGCCAGUCUAUUCUGUUCUCCAUGCUGCCAAGAGCGUCGACAUCUAAAGAAAUUGAUGCUGGACUUCUUUCCAUUAUUUCCUUCCCGGCCUUUGCAGUGGAAGAUGUAAACCUUGUAAAUGUGACCAAAAAUGAAAUUAUUUCUAAGCUCCAGGGGCGUUAUGGAUGCUGUCGCUUCCUUCGAGAUGGUUAUAAAACUCCAAGAGAGGACCCUAAUCGACUGCAUUAUGACCCUGCUGAACUCAAGCUCUUCGAAAACAUUGAAUGUGAGUGGCCUGUGUUUUGGACAUAUUUUAUAAUAGAUGGAGUCUUCAGUGGUGAUGCUGUUCAGGUCCAAGAAUACCGAGAGGCCCUGGAGGGAAUACUCAUCAGAGGCAAGAAUGGGAUCCGCCUGGUGCCUGAACUCUACGCUGUCCCGCCUAACAAGGUAGAUGAAGAGUACAAGAAUCCUCACACAGUAGACCGAGUUCCUAUGGGGAAGGUGCCUCAUCUGUGGGGCCAAUCCUUGUACAUCCUCAGCUCGCUGUUGGCAGAGGGAUUCCUUGCCGCUGGUGAAAUCGAUCCCUUAAAUAGAAGAUUUUCCACUUCAGUCAAACCUGAUGUUGUAGUACAAGUUACUGUUUUGGCAGAAAACAAUCACAUUAAGGACUUAUUGAGGAAACACGGGGUGAACGUCCAGAGUAUCGCGGACAUUCAUCCAAUUCAAGUCCAGCCGGGCCGGAUUCUUAGUCACAUAUAUGCCAAGCUUGGACGGAAUAAGAAUAUGAAUUUGAGUGGGCGACCGUAUCGACAUAUUGGUGUCCUUGGAACCUCUAAACUAUAUGUGAUUAGGAACCAAAUCUUUACUUUUACACCCCAGUUCACCGACCAGCAUCACUUCUACCUGGCCCUCGACAAUGAGAUGAUCGUGGAGAUGCUAAGGAUCGAGCUGGCCUACCUGUGCACCUGCUGGAGGAUGACGGGCAGACCCACACUCACCUUCCCCAUCAGUCGCACCAUGCUCACAAAUGAUGGCUCAGACAUUCAUUCUGCUGUGCUCUCCACAAUUAGAAAACUAGAGGAUGGAUAUUUUGGAGGAGCCAGAGUAAAAUUAGGGAACCUUUCGGAAUUUCUCACCACAUCGUUCUACACAUAUCUGACUUUUCUGGAUCCAGACUGUGAUGAGAAGUUGUUUGACAAUGCCAGCGAAGGGACUUUCAGUCCUGAUAGUGAUUCAGAUUUGGUAGGAUAUCUGGAAGACACCUGUAAUCAAGAAAGCCAAGACGAACUUGACCAUUAUAUCAACCACCUUCUGCAAAGCACAUCGUUGAGGUCCUAUCUGCCUCCUCUUUGUAAGAACACAGAAGACCGCCAUGUCUUCAGUGCUAUCCACUCCACGCGGGACAUACUUUCUGUGAUGGCAAAAGCAAAGGGUUUGGAAGUUCCAUUUGUUCCCAUGACUUUGCCGACUAAAGUUCUAAGUGCCCACCGUAAAUCACUGAAUCUUGUUGAUUCUCCUCAGCCACUCCUAGAAAAGGUUCCUGAAAGUGACUUUCAGUGGCCCAGAGAUGACCAUGGUGACGUGGACUGUGAGAAGCUGGUUGAGCAGCUAAAAGAUUGUUCGAACCUACAGGACCAAGCAGACAUUCUGUACAUUCUUUAUGUCAUAAAGGGUCCCAGCUGGGACACAAAUCUCUCUGGACAGCACGGGGUCACCGUUCAAAACCUUCUUGGUGAGCUCUAUGGGAAAGCCGGCUUGAACCAGGAGUGGGGUCUGAUUCGCUACAUCUCAGGCCUUCUCAGGAAGAAAGUGGAGGUCCUGGCUGAGGCCUGCACAGACCUGCUUUCGCACCAGAAGCAGCUCACCGUGGGCCUGCCGCCCGAGCCCCGGGAGAAGAUCAUCUCUGCGCCCCUUCCCCCAGAGGAGCUCACAAAACUCAUCUACGAGGCCAGUGGGCAGGACAUCAGCAUUGCCGUCCUCACGCAGGAGAUUGUGGUUUACCUGGCCAUGUAUGUCAGGGCGCAGCCCAGCCUCUUUGUGGAGAUGCUGAGACUCCGGAUUGGACUGAUCAUUCAGGUGAUGGCCACGGAGCUGGCACGGAGCCUGAACUGCUCAGGAGAAGAGGCUUCUGAAAGUUUGAUGAACCUCAGCCCUUUCGAUAUGAAAAAUCUCCUGCACCAUAUUCUAAGUGGGAAAGAGUUUGGCGUUGAAAGAAGUGUGCGCCCUAUCCACUCCUCCACAUCCAGCCCUACCAUCUCCAUCCACGAGGUGGGCCAUACCGGAGUCACCAAAACUGAGAGGAGUGGCAUUAACAGACUGAGGAGUGAAAUGAAACAGAUGACUAGGCGGUUUAGUGCUGAUGAACAGUUCUUUUCUGUGGGCCAGGCCGCGUCCAGCAGUGCGCAUUCCUCCAAGUCUGCGGUAACAGUGCCUCGGGAUUAUUGUAGGUCCAGCACCCCAUCCUCGCCCACUGGCACGUCAUCCUCAGACUCGGGAGGACAUCACAUCGGCUGGGGUGAGCGGCAGGGCCAGUGGCUGCGCAGGAGAAGGCUGGAUGGGGCCAUCAACAGGGUCCCCGUGGGAUUCUACCAGAGGGUGUGGAAGAUCCUCCAGAAGUGCCACGGUCUCUCCAUCGAUGGUUAUGUCCUCCCAUCCUCGACGACCCGAGAGAUGACCCCGCAUGAGAUCAAGUUUGCUGUCCAUGUCGAAUCGGUGCUGAACCGCGUGCCGCAGCCCGAGUACCGGCAGCUGCUGGUGGAAGCCAUCAUGGUGCUGACGCUGCUCUCGGACACGGAGAUGACCAGCAUCGGGGGCAUCAUCCACGUGGACCAGAUCGUGCAGAUGGCCAGUCAGCUGUUCUUGCAGGACCAGGUGUCAAUUGGUGCCAUGGACACCCUGGAGAAAGACCAAGCCACAGGAAUCUGCCACUUCUUUUAUGACAGCGCUCCGAGUGGGGCUUAUGGGACGAUGACCUACCUAACAAGAGCAGUGGCUUCUUAUUUGCAGGAAUUGUUGCCCAAUUCGGGCUGCCAGAUGCAAUAGGGUCUCACCUGGAAACAUGAUCACACUCUCAAUCUGUCACGUGCCCCCUAGCCUUACUGGGAACCUUCUGUCCCCCAAGAUCCCCUGUGCUAUCAGGAAAGCAUGUCCCAUCAGAAACACUCUCGGGGGGCAAUGGUAGCACUCACCCUGAAACUGAUGUAUGUUAAAGCCACAGAGAUAGAGCUGAGGAGUCCUGUGUUCCCCCGCAAGGAGCACCCCGGGAUCAUUUUCUAGGUUCAUUUCUCUGGAACAUUUGCUGUAGCAUCUGGUCUCACGGACUCUGAGGAGGAAUUGGAAAUUGGUCUCUUUUGAGUGCAGAGGGAACUGAGACGCCAGCUUAAAUUGGCUCUUGCAGAGAGUUACAGAAAUAGUUUCGAUGAGCUAGUGACACAUCCUAAAGAUGCAAAGAUCCUCCUGGCGGCAGUAGCCUUGACAAGGGCCACCUCUUCACAGGAUGCAGUCUGUCUGUGCACCAAACUCUUCACCAAAUAGAACACUUGUGUCUCUCUGUGGAAUGGGGGUUUUCUUGUGCCUUGCUUGCUUUCAUAGCCUUCCAUUUUAUUGGCAUGGCUGCCUUGAUGUAACAUAAUUCUCUGUCCCCAAGAUUUAGAAAAUUCCUCUUCGUUCACCUUGGCUCAUGGUCUUCCAGGGUUUUUAUCCUGGCUGUCUAUGAACUAGGGUUUUCUCCUGCCUUAGGAAAAAUACUGCAUCUUCUGGAAUCUAGAAAAAAAAAAAAAAAAAGACAAGGCUCCUCUUAUAGCCAGGCAAGCAGUUGUUUAGGGCUAGACCUGUUGUCCCCGCUCGCGUGGGGUGAACGCCCCGCAGUGGAUACUGUCCUCCUGUGCUCUGGGCGAGGCGUCAUAGGGUGAGCACAAGUCAGCAGUGCCAUGGAAGUGAACAGGCAUGUCCCCGCAGAAACAAUGCUUCCCUCUGAAAAAUAGAGCCAGGCUAGGAACCUGUACCCUCUUGGUAGAAGCACUUUGGUCUUCACUCUCUUGGGUGGGUGCAGUUGGAGGCACCGAUUGGAGGAGAGCAAGGUUGAGUCAGGUGUCAGGGUCUGGCAAAUCUUUUGCCAAUGCCCUAGCAAUGGAGUUUCUCUCCGGGCAUUGUCUUACCUUGGGGGAAGGAAACAAAACCAAUGGGAAAACAGUUUCUGUAAAUAAUAAACCUUGAAAGACAAAUGCUCA